AGGAGCUGGUGGGGAGUAACCCUCCGCAGAGGAAUUGGAAAGGAAUAGCAAUUGCACUGCUUGUCAUUCUGGUCAUCUGCUCCUUGAUCGUCACCUCGGUCAUACUUCUGACACCAGCGGAAGAUAAUAGUCUGUCUCAAAAGAAGAAGGUCACUGUAGAAGAUCUCUUCAGUGAAGACUUCAAAAUUCAUGACCCCGAGGCUAAGUGGAUAAGUGAUACAGAAUUCAUCUACAGAGAACAGAAAGGAACAGUGAGACUGUGGAAUGUUGAAACAAAUACUUCUACUGUCUUAAUAGAAGGCAAAAAAAUUGAAUCAUUAAGAGCCAUCAGAUAUGAAAUAUCUCCAGAUAGAGAGUAUGCACUUUUUUCAUACAAUGUGGAACCCGGUCAGUGAACGCAUGUCAGCUCUGCACUCAGUCCUGCUGCACUUCGGUGGACUCUCACCAGAGGUCAAAGGCUAUCAGCUCACUCCUUUUGUCUGACCAAUGCCUUGGGUGGCUGCUCUCAUCCUGACUUGAGCUAAAUUGGGUGAUCUGCCUGGAGACUUAGAACCUUAUUCCUCCCCCCAACCAUUCCCACUGCCUUUGCCUUGAUCUGGACUCUUCUCUCCUCUUGCCAGGACCAAUGCUGCCGCUUUCCACCUGUCCUUCCCUCCUGUGCAUCCCACACAGCCUGCAGCUAAGCAUGGUUCUGAGCAAGACACAGCUUCAUGCAAAAUAUUGUACCUCUGCUUGAAGACCCAAUGUGAACAUUGCCCAUUGAUUUUUGUUUCUCGAUCCCCAACUUCCCAUGCCCCAAAAUAGCAUCCUGGGACCAUAGAAAUGGAAUUGAGCUUUCUAAAAUGAUUCUGCCCAUCUCCCACUUUACAGAUGAAGAAAGUGAAGUCCAGGAAGUUGACAUUGCCUCAUUCAAAAUCAUGUGACUCAUUAGCAGUAAGUCAAGCCUGUAGCCCAGCUUGUCACCAGGGCUGUUUUCUUCAUUACAUCACCAUGUCUCUUCCUCUUCACUGCCUGCGUGACUAUGUCUCGGCAGUCAAUGGAUACAGCACAGCAUUGCCAGCUUGCCAUGUACAAGGGGGACCUGUUUCAGAUAUUCCAUGGAGACCCUGGCUGGAGGAUUGCAGGAGAGUCCCAGGAGGCAGGACUGCCAAUGGCACCAGGCUUCGCAGCCAUGCACCUGCAGCCCUCAGGCAGCACUGUCCAUUGUCAUACGAGUGUGGCAGGUGUGAGGCAUCGCAUCUGCUCACCCCGGGGAUAAUGCACAGCAGCUACAGGCAGAUUUCGGGCCAGAGAGCAACCGAGUGAGCCUUGCAGCCUCUGCUGCCAGCACAGGCUUGUUCCUUCAACACUGGUGGAGAGAGACACGCUGUCAUCAGGCCCAAGAAAUACUGCCUUCCCCAUCCUAUCCCUGGUCACUGGGUGCCCGCAGAGUGUCCCAGAGGAGGGAGGGAGGGACCCUCCACUGGUUCAAAUGGCCUGUUCUCAGAGAUGCAGCAAUGGACCCUCGUGAAUACUGAACUGAUAAUCAUGGGAAGGAGACUGGCUCUCCUGGAUUCCCUCAUGAUUCCUCUGAGUGACAAUGUGAUGUUGGCCGACUGUGUCUUCUUCAGAAUAUCAUAUACACUUGAGGUCUCCAGGAGCCUCCAAUUACAUUAUUUUCCUGGCUCAUACAGUGACAAGUAAUUCUUAUCCUGGAUUCCUCGUUACUGAGACUUUUCUUGCCUUUUUUGUUAGCUUAUGAUUUAUUCUAGGACUUCCUCCAACAGGUUAUACUUAACUGUCUACCUCAGUCUCUGGAAGUUUUAAAAAUGUUCAGCUAAAUAAAAGAAGUAGAUUCUCCCUGGAAACCAAA